GGUGAUUCCCUCCGACUUGCGUCUGCUUCUCGCCAGCAGCCCCAGCAUUAUGCAGAGACUUGUGCUGCUAUUAGCCAUUUCUCUUCUACUCUAUCAAGAUCUUCCAGUGAGAAGCGAAUUUGAAUUGGACAGAAUAUGUGGUUAUGGGACUGCCCGUUGCCGGAAGAAAUGUCGCAGCCAAGAAUACAGAAUUGGAAGAUGUCCCAACACCUAUGCAUGCUGUUUGAGAAAAUGGGAUGAGAGCUUACUGAAUCGUACAAAACCCUGAAACGCAGUAGUGCUGGUCCCUAGAGUCGCUGGAAGUAGGACCUCAGUA